AGUCCCCUCGCUGUAGUCGCGGAGCUGUGUCUGUUCCCAGGAGUCCUUCGGCGGCUGUUGUGUCGGGAGCCUGAUCGCGAUGGGGACAAAGGCGCAAGUCGAGAGGAAACUGUUGUGCCUCUUCAUAUUGGCGAUCCUGUUGUGCUCCCUGGCAUUGGGCAGUGUUACAGUGCACUCUUCUGAACCUGAAGUCAGAAUUCCUGAGAAUAAUCCUGUGAAGUUGUCCUGUGCCUACUCGGGCUUUUCUUCUCCCCGUGUGGAGUGGAAGUUUGACCAAGGAGACACCACCAGACUCGUUUGCUAUAAUAACAAGAUCACAGCUUCCUAUGAGGACCGGGUGACCUUCUUGCCAACUGGUAUCACCUUCAAGUCCGUGACACGGGAAGACACUGGGACAUACACUUGUAUGGUCUCUGAGGAAGGCGGCAACAGCUAUGGGGAGGUCAAGGUCAAGCUCAUCGUGCUUGUGCCUCCAUCCAAGCCUACAGUUAACAUCCCCUCCUCUGCCACCAUUGGGAACCGGGCAGUGCUGACAUGCUCAGAACAAGAUGGUUCCCCACCUUCUGAAUACACCUGGUUCAAAGAUGGGAUAGUGAUGCCUACGAAUCCCAAAAGCACCCGUGCCUUCAGCAACUCUUCCUAUGUCCUGAAUCCCACAACAGGAGAGCUGGUCUUUGAUCCCCUGUCAGCCUCUGAUACUGGAGAAUACAGCUGUGAGGCACGGAAUGGGUAUGGGACACCCAUGACUUCAAAUGCUGUGCGCAUGGAAGCUGUGGAGCGGAAUGUGGGGGUCAUCGUGGCAGCCGUCCUUGUAACCCUGAUUCUCCUGGGAAUCUUGGUUUUUGGCAUCUGGUUUGCCUAUAGCCGAGGCCACUUUGACAAGCUGGGGGCCUGCCCCUCCAUCUUCCCAAGCCAUGCUGUCUUCUGUCCUGCUGACACUCAUGAUCCCAUUUCUUCUCUUUCAGGAACAAAGAAAGGGACUUCGAGUAAGAAGGUGAUUUACAGCCAGCCUAGUGCCCGAAGUGAAGGAGAAUUCAAACAGACCUCGUCAUUCCUGGUGUGAGCCUGGUCGGCUCACCGCCUAUCAUCUGCAUUUGCCUUACUCAGGUGCUACCGGACUCUGGCCCCUGAUGUCUGUAGUUUCACAGGAUGCCUUAUUUGUCUUCUACACCCCACAGGGCCCCCUACUUCUUCGGAUGUGUUUUUAAUAAUGUCAGCUAUGUGCCCCAUCCUCCUUCAUGCCCUCCCUCCCUUUCCUACCACUGCUGAGUGGCCUGGAACUUGUUUAAAGUGUUUAUUCCCCAUUUCUUUGAGGGAUCAGGAAGGAAUCCUGGGUAUGCCAUUGACUUCCCUUCUAAGUAGACAGCAAAAAUGGCGGGGGUCGCAGGAAUCUGCACUCAACUGCCCACCUGGCUGGCAGGGAUCUUUGAAUAGGUAUCUUGAGCUUGGUUCUGGGCUCUUUCCUUGUGUACUGACGACCAGGGCCAGCUGUUCUAGAGCGGGAAUUAGAGGCUAGAGCGGCUGAAAUGGUUGUUUGGUGAUGACACUGGGGUCCUUCCAUCUCUGGGGCCCACUCUCUUCUGUCUUCCCAUGGGAAGUGCCACUGGGAUCCCUCUGCCCUGUCCUCCUGAAUACAAGCUGACUGACAUUGACUGUGUCUGUGGAAAAUGGGAGCUCUUGUUGUGGAGAGCAUAGUAAAUUUUCAGAGAACUUGAAGCCAAAAGGAUUUAAAACCGCUGCUCUAAAGAAAAGAAAACUGGAGGCUGGGCGCAGUGGCUCACGCCUAUAAUCCCAGAGGCUGAGGCAGGCGGAUCACCUGAGGUCAGGAGUUCAAGAUCAGCCUGACCAACAUGGAGAAACCCUACUAAAAAUACAAAGUUAGCCAGGCAUAGUGGUGCAUGCCUGUAAUCCCAGCUGCUCAGGAGCCUGGCAACAAGAGCAAAACUCCAGCUCAAAAAAAAAAAGAAAGAAAAGAAAGCUGGAGCUGGUGGCUUAGGCCAUCACCCUUCCCUUGGCUGGAACUACUGGACAGACCCUUUUGAGAUGUGCCUGUGGUGCUGUGGAGAUGUGUGUAGUGGUCUUAGCUCUUUGUUGAGCUUGUGUGUGUGUUGUGUAGUCUUAGCUGUAUGCUGAAAUUGGGCGUGUGUUGGAGGGCUUCUUAGCUCUUUGGUGAGAUUGUAUUUCUAUGUGUUUGUAUCAGCUGAAUGUUGCUGGAAAUAAAACCUUGGUUUGUCAAGGCUCUUUUUUGUGGGAAGUAAGUAGGGGAAAAGGUCUUUGAGGGUUCCUAGGCUCCUUUGUACAACAGGAAAAUGCCUCAAAGCCUUGCUUCCCAGCAACCUGGGGCUGGUUCCCAGUGCCUGGUCCUGCCCCUUCCUGGUUCUUAUCUCAAGGCAGAGCUUCUGAAUUUCAGGCCUUCAUUCCAGAGCCCUCUUGUGGCCAGGCCUUCCUUUGCUGGAGGAAGGUACACAGGGUGAAGCUGAUGCUGUACUUGGGGGAUCUCCUUGGCCUGUUCCACCAAGUGAGAGAAGGUACUUACUCUUGUACCUCCUGUUCAGCCAGGUGCAUUAACAGACCUCCCUACAGCUGUAGGAACUACUGUCCCAGAGCUGAGGCAAGGGGAUUUCUCAGGUCAUUUGGAGAACAAGUGCUUUAGUAGUAGUUUAAAGUAGUAACUGCUACUGUAUUUAGUGGGGUGGAAUUCAGAAGAAAUUUGAAGACCAGAUCAUGGGUGGUCUGCAUGUGAAUGAACAGGAAUGAGCCGGACAGCCUGGCUGUCAUUGCUUUCUUCCUCCCCAUUUGGACCCUUCUCUGCCCUUACAUUUUUGUUUCUCCAUCUACCACCAUCCACCAGUCUAUUUAUUAACUUAGCAAGAGGACAAGUAAAGGGCCCUCUUGGCUUGAUUUUGCUUCUUUCUUUCUGUGGAGGAUAUACUAAGUGCGACUUUGCCCUAUCCUAUUUGGAAAUCCCUAACAGAAUUGAGUUUUCUAUUAAGGAUCCAAAAAGAAAAACAAAAUGCUAAUGAAGCCAUCAGUCAAGGGUCACAUGCCAAUAAACAAUAAAUUUUCCAGAAGAAAUGAAAUCCAACUAGACAAAUAAAGUAGAGCUUAUGAAAUGGUUCAGUAAAGAUGAGUUUGUUGUUUUUUGUUUUGUUUUGUUUUGUUUUUUUAAAGACGGAGUCUCGCUCUGUCACCCAGGCUGGAGUGCAGUGGUAUGAUCUUGGCUCACUGUAACCUCCGCCUCCCGGGUUCAAGCCAUUCUCCUGCCUCAGUCUCCUGAGUAGCUGGGAUUACGGGUGCGUGCCACCAUGCCUGGCUAAUUUUUGUGUUUUUAGUAGAGACAGGGUUUCACCAUGUUGGUCGGGCUGGUCUCAAACUCCUGACCUCUUGAUCCGCCUGCCUUGGCCUCCCAAAGUGAUGGGAUUACAGAUGUGAGCCACCGUGCCUAGCCAAGGAUGAGAUUUUUAAAGUAUGUUUCAGUUCUGUGUCAUGGUUGGAAGACAGAGUAGGAAGGAUAUGGAAAAGGUCAUGGGGAAGCAGAGGUGAUUCAUGGCUCUGUGAAUUUGAGGUGAAUGGUUCCUUAUUGUCUAGGCCACUUGUGAAGAAUAUGAGUCAGUUAUUGCCAGCCUUGGAAUUUACUUCUCUAGCUUACAAUGGACCUUUUGAACUGGAAAACACCUUGUCUGCAUUCACUUUAAAAUGUCAAAACUAAUUUUUAUAAUAAAUGUUUAUUUUCACAUUGAGUUUGUUUAAAUCCUGAAGUUCUUACCUUAAGAGAAUUGGGACUCCUAGAGUGAUUGGACAUUCAAAAUAUUCCUGAUAGUCUUGUUAAUUAAGAGAUUAGGAUAUCUUUCCAUUACCUUGAUAAUUACGUUUUAAUUUAGCUUUUUUCAUUGGCCUGUGUUUAAAUGCAAAUAACCCCACAAUGGACAUUUCCUAUGUUAAAGUGACAUUUAGGGGAUAAAAAAUGAGAGCAGUUCCAUGGAUUUUGGUGUUUCCCCUGAGACAUGAACUCAGCAUAAUCUGGGAUAAAAUGAUUGAGUGUUAAGGAUGUGUUUGUUGUUCCUGUCGUUUUUUUAUUUUCUUCAAAGUAUACAACAUGGUUUGAUAUGCACAUACAUUUGUGUAAUGAUUGCCAUGGUCAAUUAACACAUCACCAUUUUUGUGUGUGUGUGUGUGUGUGUGUGUGAGGGAGUCUUGCUCCGUUGCCAGGCUGGAGUGCAAUGGUACAACCUUGGCUCACUGCAACCUCCACCUCCUGGGUUCAAGCAAUUCUCUUGCCUCAGCCUCCUAAGUAGCUGGGACUAUAGGCGUGUGCCACCAUGCCCAGCUAAUUUUUGUAUUUUUAGUAGAGACGGGGUUUCACCAUGUUGGCCAGGAUGAUCUCGAUCCCUUGACCUCAUGAUCCGCCCACCUCGGCCUCCCAAAGUGCUGGGAUUACAGGCGUGAGUCACUGCACCCGGCCACAUCACCUCCCAUGUUCUAUCUUACGUAUUCAGAACUUGUUCAUCUUGUAACUGAAAGCGUGUACCCUUUGACCAACACUGUUUUUCCUGUCUUAACAGGAUCUACAGAUCAAGGACAGGGGAGGGGAUAGUGGAGGAAAACGGAGUUAGUCUGUUUCUAAAUGAGGGGACAGUAUGUUUCUUGGGGCCUGAGGACAGCUUAAUAAAGUAGACAAAUGAAGAAAAACAACAAUUUGCAUUAAAAAAUAUCCAAUUCUUUA